CCCUGGGAGCCCGCACCCGUCUCUGGUGCCAGGGCGUUGUCGGGGGUCCCAAGAGAGCGGGGUGGGGAAGGUGAAGGGAGCGCGGCUGGAAAAAUGGGGAUUAGGGUGGCGGAACAGGCACUUGUCAGGAGUGAAGAGACAGCGGAGAGGGUACUGGGCUGAAUUCUUUCGUGCCGAGCAGGUCCCUCCGGUUCCCAACUCACCCGGGUGGAGCAGGCGCGGGCCGAACCCGGGAGGAGAGUGUCGGGGAUCCGCGAAGGAGCCUCCUGGGGAUGGGGCGGGGGAUGGACAAAGCGCUGCCCCCGGCUGGACGCGCUCUGGCUGCAGCCCGGCUGGCAUCCGGAGCUGGGAACAGCAGCCCGCGGGGUGCCCGGGUCAGGGCUCAACCCUAGCGGGUCUCUGGCGAGGCCGGGGGCGCAGCCCGCGGGGCGCCACUCAGGCCGUCCAGCUGCCGCGCGGUCCAGCGCUGACCCGAGCCCGGGAGGCAGCUGCGCUCUAAGGUUUGCGCUCCUGUUUGCGAGGUGUCUUCAUAUAACAAAUGCGAGCAAUAACAAACAUCCAUAGAACUCGAAUUCCAGAAACGGGAAUUCUUUUUUCCAAGUUCACAGACCUUUAGUUAAUCUUUUAAAGGAACUGAGGCGUUGUGUUGGACCAAAGCCAAAACGAUUUUACCUUAGACCAUGGAAAAUAGCCUAAGGCUCUUUCAGCAGAAUUUUGCAGUCCGAAUGCAAUUUUAGAUUUCAGAUUUCUCAAGGGAAGAGAAACUCUGCUGUUAGAAUUUGGAAGGGAGGGUGGUGCAUGCCUGUGUGUUUGUCAGCUGAGCAGAGCUGUAUUUAUCUUUCCAAUUCAAAUUGUGCCAGAUUCUGGCUUUAAGAACAAACCAUGGGAAUAUUUGAGAACAUGGAAUCAUGCUGCUGUUCCACGAUCACAGCAAAACAGACAAUAGUUGAUAUUGUAUCAUUGCAGGAGGAAAAAGAAUUACAUAUAUUUUAUUCUUUUGUGUGAUUGUCAUCCUUUGUGAAAAGAAUGAUGUGUAUUUUCAUAAAGCAAAAAAUUAUUCAAACAAAGAAACCUUAUUUAAAUGUACAAGUCAGACUUUUAAUAUCCUUUGAAUUCCCUGCAGUUCCUCCUAUUAUUCUUGAGAACUAUCUACUUUCUUAAAAUACUUAAAAUCUAUUCAGAAGGUUUCAUUUGUCUAGGUGUCAGAUAUAGAAGAGUUUAUAAGAAAAUUCCAGUAAACCUUUAAAAAGAUAUUAUUUUUUAUAAGUUGCCAUAGUUUAAUAAAGAACUUUUAUUUUUCACACUUUUUACUCAGAGAUUAAAGUUCUGUGUUUCAGCCUGGAAAUUCUGAUGGUGGGAGAUACAACUAAUACAAAAGAGAAUGAGUAAAUAUAGUAAUUAGGUCUGCUCAUUGUGUUUUUCAGGAAAAAGGAAGGGAAAGGAGAGGUCUAACCACAUGGAAUGGAGAAAAAUCUGAAUUUUAGACUCAAAACUACAUUGUUUCUAUUACCACAAAUUGUGCUGCAUCUUCUCUUUCUUCAAAAAAUUUUGGACAGCAAUUUUACACUAAGUGUUACAAGGAAAGGCUAUCGGUAACAACUGACCUGCCACAAAGUUAGAAGAAAGGAUUGAUUCAAGAAAUGAUGAAGUUACUCUGCCAUGUAUUGGGAUGGAUUCCAAAGACUAUAAUAUGGAUUUAGAGCUCGACGAGUAUUAUAACAAGACACUUGCCACAGAGAAUAAUACUGCUGCCACUCGGAAUUCUGAUUUCCCAGUCUGGGAUGACUAUAAAAGCAGUGUAGAUGACUUACAGUAUUUUCUGAUUGGGCUCUAUACAUUUGUAAGUCUUCUUGGCUUUAUGGGGAAUCUACUUAUUUUAAUGGCUCUCAUGAAAAAGCGUAAUCAGAAGACUACGGUAAACUUCCUCAUAGGCAAUCUGGCCUUUUCUGAUAUCUUGGUUGUGCUGUUUUGCUCACCUUUCACACUGACGUCUGUCUUGCUGGAUCAGUGGAUGUUUGGCAAAGUCAUGUGCCAUAUUAUGCCUUUUCUUCAAUGUGUGUCAGUUUUGGUUUCAACUUUAAUUUUAAUAUCAAUUGCCAUUGUCAGGUAUCAUAUGAUAAAACAUCCCAUAUCUAAUAAUUUAACAGCAAACCAUGGCUACUUUCUGAUAGCUACUGUCUGGACACUAGGUUUUGCCAUCUGUUCUCCCCUUCCAGUGUUUCACAGUCUUGUGGAACUUCAAGAAACAUUUGGUUCAGCAUUGCUGAGCAGCAGGUAUUUAUGUGUUGAGUCAUGGCCAUCUGAUUCAUACAGAAUUGCCUUUACUAUCUCUUUAUUGCUAGUUCAGUAUAUUCUGCCCUUAGUUUGUCUUACUGUAAGUCAUACAAGUGUCUGCAGAAGUAUAAGCUGUGGAUUGUCCAACAAAGAAAACAGACUUGAAGAAAAUGAGAUGAUCAACUUAACUCUUCAUCCAUCCAAAAAGAGUGGGCCUCAGGUGAAACUCUCUGGCAGCCAUAAAUGGAGUUAUUCAUUCAUCAAAAAACACAGAAGAAGAUAUAGCAAGAAGACAGCAUGUGUGUUACCUGCUCCAGAAAGACCUUCUCAAGAGAACCACUCCAGAAUACUUCCAGAAAACUUUGGCUCUGUAAGAAGUCAGCUCUCUUCAUCCAGUAAGUUCAUACCAGGGGUCCCCACUUGCUUUGAGAUAAAACCUGAAGAAAAUUCAGAUGUUCAUGAAUUGAGAGUAAAACGUUCUGUUACAAGAAUAAAAAAGAGAUCUCGAAGUGUUUUCUACAGACUGACCAUACUGAUAUUAGUAUUUGCUGUUAGUUGGAUGCCACUACACCUUUUCCAUGUGGUAACUGAUUUUAAUGACAAUCUUAUUUCAAAUAGGCAUUUCAAGUUGGUGUAUUGCAUUUGUCAUUUGUUGGGCAUGAUGUCCUGUUGUCUUAAUCCAAUUCUAUAUGGGUUUCUUAAUAAUGGGAUUAAAGCUGAUUUAGUGUCCCUUAUACACUGUCUUCAUAUGUAAUAAUUCUCACUGUUUACCAAGGAAAGAACAAAUGCUGGGGUCAUAUAAAAUAUAUUUAUGAUAACUAUUUACAUAUAAUAAAUAGAAAUUUUGUUAACAUGGAAUUUAAUUUAUGUGAAAGAGUUCUGGAUUCAAAUGUCAGUUCAUAAUAUAUGGAAGAUAAUUUUAUGUGUUAUAGUAGGAUUAAUUUAUUUAGUUGUGCAGUCAGUGUCAAUCCAAUCUGUAAUUUCACUUUAGAAGGUUGUAUUACCUUCCACUUCCAUGUUGUCUUAUAAACAAAUGAAUUGUAUUUUUUGUUGAAAGUAAAAGUUAUAUCUAACCAA